GCUCCUCGCCGUCCGCGCUGCAGUGCGAAGGGCUCGAAGAUGGCCGGUUGGCAGAGCUACGUGGAUAACCUGAUGUGCGAUGGCUGCUGCCAGGAGGCCGCCAUUGUCGGCUACUGCGACGCCAAAUACGUCUGGGCAGCCACGGCCGGGGGCGUCUUUCAGAGCAUUACGCCAAUAGAAAUAGAUAUGAUUGUAGGAAAAGACCGGGAAGGUUUCUUUACCAACGGUUUGACUCUUGGCGCGAAGAAAUGCUCAGUGAUCAGAGAUAGUCUAUACGUCGAUGGUGACUGCACAAUGGACAUCCGGACAAAGAGUCAAGGUGGGGAGCCAACAUACAAUGUGGCUGUCGGCAGAGCUGGUAGAGUCUUGGUCUUUGUAAUGGGAAAAGAAGGGGUCCAUGGAGGCGGAUUGAAUAAGAAGGCAUACUCAAUGGCAAAAUACUUGAGAGACUCUGGGUUCUAGCUGCUAGGCAGACUGUUAAGUAUUAGGGGAAAAUUGCUCUUAAACUUUCCUAGCUAUAAGCUUAAGUCUUAAUUCUGGAAAUUUUAUUAGCAAUGCAGGGUGAUGGGGUAUGAACCUGUGUCUCCUUUGUAUCCCUCUGUUGGUGGGGAAAGGUGUCUUUCUUUCUGCCCUCCCCCCCCAAAAUAAUUCUGUUCACUUUUGUUUUGUUUCCUUGUGUACUCCAGCAUUGGUUAUAGUCAUGGGAAAGGAAGGUGUCCACGGAGGCACACUUAACAAGAAAGCAUAUGAACUCGCUUUAUACCUGAGGAGGUCUGAUGUGUAAGCAGCCUCUCCCCAUCUACCUAGCAACUGUCUUCAUCAACAACCCUAAUUAUGGUCACAAUGCUACCAAACUGUAGAUGGUAGCUAAUUUUUCUUUACCUAUUUUCUAAUGUCAUGAUUCCUGUUUGCCCAAUGGAUCAUUUGUAUGUUAACCACUGUAUGUAACCAACCCUUAUCUGGCAACAUAAUUGCAGCACAAUAAUGAUUUGCAUGAUACCUUGAAAUUGGGGGGAGGGGGCAUGCCAAGUUGGGCAUCACUUUGUCUUAGCAAUUAAUGGGAUAUUGAUUACUAAAAUAAGUUAAUAUUAAGCAAGGUGCCGGUUGUACAAUCUCUGAUCAGUGUCUUUUCAGCACUUUGAGCAUUUACUUGGCUCAUUUAGUCUUCCUUUUGUAGCGCAUGGUUGGGAGGAAAAAGUGCAUGCAUCAUUCCUUCACUCUUCUCUUUUUCCCGCCCCCCCUCCCUUCGCACAUAGGCAUUUGGUUUGCUUCCAUCUUUUUUUAUGCAGUGCCUGUUUUUUUUUAACCAAUUAAAAUCCCUUUUGUUGAUGAGCUAUUGAGAGCUGCAGUAGUUUGCUUUUAGUAUUGUUGUUGCACUUGAGCAGAGACAAACCUUUAUUCAUAGUGUCUACAGGACAUAUGAAGAGUGCAAUGGCAAAACAAGAGCAAAAAGCACUUCCUCCCAUGACCUUACAGUAACCAUACUGAUUGAAUCCCCAGGGACAUUCCAUCAUUGCAAUAGCUCAGAUUUUUCUUCCUUUUUCUUUGCACACCAGCUCUACUCUUUAGUAAAAUUGUAAAAGGCUGCCAUUAUGGACAUUAGGUAUCCCAACAUAACCAUCUGGAGUGUGUCCAGUUUGUUCUUCAUAGGACCAAUUUUUAUUUGCAGCUUGAGUUUUUAUAUGAAGUUGCAUUAUUGUGGACUUGGCUGUCUUGUGAUGAAUUUUUUUCAUAUGUAUUCUGUGCCAUACUAUUGUUAAAAUGAACUGUUGCUAUUGUGAGAUGGAUUUUAACUGACCUAUUAAGGGUUUCUUUCGAAUGGCACUACUUUAGGGACAUUCUAGUAUUUGCUUCUAUUGUUUGGGCCUUGUGGAUAAUGUACAGAUUUAAAAACAAAUCUUGUUGCUGAUUUGUCCAUUUCUUUCCCUGCACUUUGUUACAUCUGGGAUACAGUCUAACUCAUCUGAUUUAAUAUGCAUUUAAAAAAAUGCCAUAACUAUUAAACACCUUGUUUACAGACAGAUGAAAUAAAUUUAUUCCAACCAAA